CCCUGAGGGCCCUUUCUCUUUCCAUCUCAGGAACUCAAACAUGACCAGGAAGAUCUUCACAAAUACCAGGGAGCGGUGGAGGCAGCAGAAUGUCAACAGCGCCUUUGCCAAGCUGAGGAAGCUCAUCCCCACUCACCCUCCAGACAAAAAGCUGAGCAAAAAUGAAACGCUUCGCCUGGCAAUGAGGUAUAUCAACUUCUUGGUCAAGGUCUUGGGGGAGCAAAGCCUGCAACAAACGGGAGUGGCUGCUCAGGGGAACAUUCUGGGGCUCUUCCCUCAAGGACCCCACCUGCCAGGCCUGGAGGACAGAACUCUGCUUGAGAACUACCAGGUUCCUUCACCUGGUCCAAGCCACCACAUUCCUUAGUGUGGCUCUGGCUGUCAUCUCCCAGGGCAGCACUUGCCCAGAAAUCACUGCCUGUGGACAGACUUUUGCAUGUUCCAGAGUUGACCUGAUGAUAACUCGUGAAGCAUGAAUUCUAGCUUCCUGGGAGGUGGCUCAGAGACAGCUGCAGGGAGCUGAAAGAAGCCAUGAGGAAUGUCACUUGUGGGCCGCCACCCCCCAGGGAUGUCAGGUAGAGCGGCCUACCUCUGCCUAUUUUAAAUCCAGGUUCUGCAUAAGACUUUUGGAGAAAAAAUUCUAAAUAAAAAAAAAAAAAGGCUGAAAA